ACUCCCACCAGCUCGCAGCCCUCCUUCGGACCCUCGAUCCGAGAGCGCCCCAGCCAGAGCUUGUGCCCAUGCCCCUGUCCCGCAGGGGAAGGGGAUCCCGCCUGGCCGGCUCUCGAGCGGCGACUAGUAACCUCCCGCGGGCGACAGCCCUCUCCCCAAAGAGUGCCGGCCGCGGGGCCCUGUCUAUAAGCCACGCGCAACUCCUCACCCGGCGGCGCCAUUCCUCCGAGCAGGUCCCGCCGGAGUCCGAGCCGCGGGCUGACUUCCGCUCGGGAAAGUGGCUCCAAGAGCCCGCCACAGGGGACGCCAGGGACUCGCGGCAGGCUCUGCGGGCCAGGAUGAGUUCUAAGCACAGGAUCUGUAGUCAGGAAGAAGUAGUGAUCCCCUGUGCCUAUGACAGUGAUUCAGAAAGUGUGGAUUUGGAGCUGAGCAACUUAGAGAUUAUUAAAAAAGGCUCAAGUAGCAUUGAACUGACAGACUUGGACAUCCCUGACAUCCCUGGACUCCAUUGUGAGCCCCUGUCACAUAGCCCCAGACACCUGACCCAACAGGACCCGCUCAGUGAGGCCAUUGUUGAGAAACUGAUCCAGUCCAUCCAGAAGGUUUUCAAUGGUGAGCUAAAGGGUGAACUUGAAAAGCUGAAAUUCCUAGGAGAUCUGUCUUCUCUCAGCCAAGCUUUACCUUAUGAUGAAACCGCAAAAUCAUUCAUUCACAGCCACAUAGCAGACAUUGUGCAUACCUUAAAUGUACUGGUACAAGAGGAACGCCCGCAUUCUCUGUCCAGUUCCAUGCGCCAGGAGGUCUUUGUCACCAUCGCUGAUCUCAGUUACCAAGAUGUCCAUUUGCUGUUGGGCUCUGAAGAUCGAGCUGAGUUGUUCAGUCUUACCAUCAAGAGUAUAAUCACUCUGCCCUCUGUAAGGACCCUUACCCAGAUACAGGAAAUCAUGCCCAAUGGGACCUGCAACACAGAGUGUCUUUACAGGCAGACGUUUCAGGCAUUCUCUGAGAUGCUCCAGAGUUUGGUGGUAAAAGACCCACAUUUGGAAAAUCUUGACACCAUUAUUAAGCACUUGGUCCCCUGGUUACAGUCAGUCAAAGACCAUGAGCGGGAACGGGCCACGGCCAGCAUGGCUCAAGUUCUGAAGUGCCUAUCCAAACAUCUCAACUUGAAGCUUCCACUGCGAUUCCAAAGACUUGGACACCUAGUGGCUCUGAUGGCACUGCUCUGUGGGGACCCACAGGAAAAGGUGGCUGAGGAGGCUGCAGAGGGCAUUCACUCCCUGCUGCAUAUCACCCUGAGGCUGAAGUAUAUCACUCAUGACAAGAAAGAUCAGCAAAACUUGAAAAGAGCAUUGACAAAAUGUCGAGAAUUCCUGGAGCUCCACAGCUCUGCCGCUAAAUGCUUCUACAACUGUCCCUUCAGAAUUGCCCAGGUCUUUGAAGGUUUUCUUGAUUCAAAUGAGCUCUGCCAGUUUAUAAUGACUACAUUUGAUACCCUGAAAACCCUGAAACAUCCCUGCAUCCAGCGAUCAGCAGGAGAAUUACUGCUAACUUUGGCAAAAAAUACAGAGUCCCAAUUUGAGAAGGUGCCAGAAAUUAUGGGAGUUAUCUGUGCCCAGUUAUCCAUAAUCAGCCAGCCUAGAGUCCGCCAACAAAUCAUAAAUACCGUGAGUUUAUUUAUAUCCAGACCCAAGUACACAGAUAUAGUGCUCAGCUUCCUUCUGUGUCAUCCAGUGCCGUAUAACAGGCACCUGGCUGAGGUGUGGAGAAUGCUGUCGGUGGAGCUUCCCAGCACGACCUGGAUUCUGUGGAGGCUCCUGAGGAAGCUGCAGAAAUGCCAUAAUGAGCCUGCACAGGAGAAGAUGGCAUAUGUGGCUGUGGCUGCAACAGAUGCCCUUUAUGAGGUGUUUUUGGGAAACAGGCUUCGAGCAGCUACGUUCCGACUCUUUCCUCAGCUUCUCAUGACACUGCUUAUCCAGAUUCAUCACAGCAUCGGCCUCACCAUGUCUGAUGUCGACAUCCCAAGUGGCCUGUACACAGAACAGGAAGUGCCUUCAGAGGUCACCCCUUUGUGCUUUGCCAUGCAGGCUACAAAGACUCUCCUCCUCAGAACAUGCUGCUUGCAGGAAUUCAACAUCAUGGAAAAGAAUAAAGGAUGGGCUCUCCUGGGAGGAAAAGAUGGCCAUCUUCAGGGACUAUUUCUCCUUGCCAACGCAUUGCUGGAAAGAAAUCAGCUCCUUGCACAGAAGGUCAUGUACUUAUUAGUCCCUCUUCUUAACCGAGGGAAUGAUAAACAUAAACUCACAUCUGCAGGCUUUUUUGUGGAGCUUCUCCGGAGUCCAGUGGCCAAGAGACUGCCCAGCAUAUACUCUGUUGCCCGCUUUAAAGACUGGCUACAAGAUGGAAAUCAUCUCUUUAGAAUUCUCGGCCUGAGGGGACUGUACAAUCUUGUUGGACACCAGGAGAUGAGAGAAGACAUCAAGAGCCUGUUGCCAUACAUUGUAGACAGCUUGCGUGAAACCGAUGAGAAGAUCGUUCUGUCAGCCAUCCAGAUACUCCUGCAACUUGUUAGAACAAUGGAUUUCACUACCCUGGCUGCCAUGAUGAGGACCCUGUUCUCCUUAUUUGGUGAUGUGAGAUCUGAUGUUCAUCGUUUCUCCGUGACUCUCUUUGGAGCCGCCAUAAAGUCUGUAAAAAACCCAGAUAAGAAGAGUAUAGAGAACCAAGUCCUGGACAGCUUGGUCCCACUACUUCUGUAUUCUCAGGAUGAAAAUGAUGCAGUAGCUGAGGAGAGCAGGCAAGUCCUAACUAUAUGUGCCCAGUUCCUGAAGUGGAAGCUGCCCCAAGAAGUGUACUCCAAAGAUCCCUGGCACAUCAAACCUACUGAAGCAGGAACAAUCUGCAGAUUCUUUGAAAAAAAGUGCAAGGGGAAAAUUAACAUCCUAGAACAAACACUGAUGUACUCCAAGAACCCAAAACUUCCCAUCAGAAGAUCAGCAGUCUUGUUUGUAGGCCUUUUAUCGAAGUACAUGGAUCACAAUGAGCUCAGGAGGAUGGGUACUGACUGGAUAGAGGACGAUCUGAGAGACCUGCUGUGUGACCCUGAGCCCUCGCUGUGCAUCAUCGCUUCCCAGACUCUGUUACUAGUCCAGAUGGCGAGGGCCGAACCAAAACCUAAGCAGAGAGUGAACUGGUUGCAGAAGCUCAUGGGCAGGUCCUCUGCCUAGAAACACAAGGCAAGCAACAUCAGAGACAGAAUCUUGCUAUGUUGUGCGGCAAGCUAGUCUUGAACUCAUGGCCUCAAGUCAUCCUCCUGUGUCAGCCUCCCAAAGUGCUGGGAUUACAAGCAUGCACCACGGCACCCAGCAGAAUUCCAGUCUUGAGAAACAGGUCAAGGACAGCUUCAAAAGAGAUUCUAAAUAAAUGUUAAUGUUACAAUGUUAGUAUGUCUGCUUAAUUGCCAACAAUAUUAAGAAUAAAGUAACUUUUUUUUUUUUUUUGA